AUGAGCCGGGAGACUCGCCGUGGGGCCUUGCCCAGGCUGCGCCGGGGAGAGCAGGCGGCUAAGAUGCCGGGUCGCUGCGUGGGGCCCAGCAGGUCGGGGCGGGGGGUUCGGCGGCCGUGGGGGAAGAGACGGGGCGCAGGGACGUCCCGAGGCCGUGGAGCAAGGCGCCGGGCGAAGCCCUCGGAGUGGGAGACGCGCUGUGUGAGUGCAGAAAGGCCACAGGGCCGUCAGCGGCCAUGGGGGACGAGACAAGCGGCGGAGACAGCCGACGCCGCCGGGGCGAAUGAGGCUUUGGGAGCUCCUGGGACCCCAGGCUCCAUCGAGGCUGCAAGGGACCCUGGGGCUGUGUGGGUGAACGGGGCUGUGGGGGAGCCCGAGGUGGUGGGGCUUGCCGGGGCUGUGUGGGUGACCGGGUCUGGGGAGGAGGAGACCGAAGAUAGAAGUCCCCGGGGCUGCGAGAGAAAAGGUCGCCCGGGAUCUCUGGGCCAUGAGAGCAUUCUGCACCUGUGGCUGAAGGUGCAGGCUAUGAGGGCCGCCUCGGGAUGUGGGGAAGGAAGUAGAGUCGAGCUCCAUCCCGUGCCUGCAGGAGAGGGACCUGUCGAAAGGGGUGUUCCUGGCCGAGCUUCCUGGGUAGAGACAAGCCGCGGCGGUCUUACAGGGCCCUGGGUGAAGGAACAGGCAAGGGGGAUCCCUCGGGCCCCCUCAGGGCCCACAGCUCUGGGCUUAGGGGCAGCUUACGAGAGAGCCUUAGGCUUCUGUGGACAGGGACAGGCUGGGAGGGUGCCUCCUGCGAGUGUGCCUGGGGCUUUGGCGUCAAGUUCUGAAAUGGCCCCGCACCUGUGGAGGGGAGAAGCUGUGGGGGUUCCUGAGACUGGGGAGGAGAUAGGCUAUGGGUUUGUCUCAGGCCCUUGUGAAAAAGAACAGACUAUGGGCGAGCCUGGGACCGUGGGGUGGACUGGGGCUGUGGGAGCGCCCAGAGCCAUGGAGGGAGAGCUCGGCUGUGGCGGUGCUGCAGGUCUGUGGGGGAGAGGACAGUCCCCGCAGAUUCCUGGGGCUCUGACACAUGAAGCAGUCUGUGGGGCCACCCCUGGCGUAUGGGGGAGGGGACAGGCUGUGGGGGUGUCCGAUGCUGUGGAGGAGGAGCCUACUUCUGUGGGUGCCGCAGGUGUGUGUUACAGGAGACAGGCUGUGGAGGAGACAGACUCUGUGGGUAUGCCCGGCCCGUGGGGCACAGGAUACUCUGUUGGGGUGCCCUGUGCUGCUGAAGAGGAAACUAGAUGUGGAGGUGACCCAGGGUUCAGGGAAAGGGGACAGCCUGUGUGGGUGGAGACAGGCUCUGGGGGUGAUCCAGGGUCACGGGGAGCUGCGCAGACUGCAGAGUCAUCAUGUCCUGGGGAGCAGGCAGCAGGUUCUGGGGGUGCCCCAGGCCUGUGGGGGAUACAACAGGCUACAGGGGUACCCAGGGCCUUGGGGAAGGACACGGGCUGUGUGAGUGUCCCAGGGCUGUGGGGAGCGGGACAGAUGGUAAGGGUGCCCCAGGCUGUGGUGGUACCUGGAGCCCUGGGAGAAGAGCUGAGCCACAGCGGGGGCCUGGGCCUGUGGGACGGACAGCAAGCUCUUGGGGGGCCCCCAGCCGAGGCAGUGCCUGGGCUUGGAGAGGAGACCUGUAGUGGGAAUGUUCUGAGCCCGUGGGAAAGGAGGCAGGCUGUGGGGGAGCCAGAGAGUCUGGGGCCUCCAGCUUUAGGGGUCCCUGGGUCAGUGGAUCAGGAGGCUGGCUGUGGAGAUGUUGCAUGUCAGUGUGGGAGGAGGCAGGCUGUGGGGGUGUCUGAGACGGUGGGCAUACCCAGGGCAGCAGAUGUGCCCCGGCAGGGGUGUGCCGCAGCAGGGGUCCUCAUGGCAAUGGGUGUGCCCGGCUCUGGAAAGGUGCCUGCCAGAGUGCCUGCUGCUGUGUGGGCGUCUGGUCCUGUGUGUCAGGAAGGCAGCUCUAGAGACAUUUUGAACCUGUGGGAAAGGACUCGGGCUGCCAGAAUAUCUGUGGCUUCGGGGGGACCCGUGGCUCGGGAGGAGCUGUGGUCUGGCGGGGAGGAAUCCGUGGCUUCAGGGGGACCCGUGGCUCAGGAGGAGCUGUGGUCAGGCGGGGAGGAAUCCGUGGCUUCAGGGGGACACGUGGCUCGGGAGAAGCUGUGGUCUGGCGGGGAGGAUUGUGGUUCUGGGGCCUUCCCGGGCCCAUGGGGGAGGAGACAGACUAUUGGGGUUCCUGUGGUGCCUGAGGGGCCUGGGCUUGGGGGGGAGACUGACUCUGGGGGUAUCCCAAGACCCUGGGGACAGAGACAGAGGGUCAGGGCUCCUGUGGCCACCGAAGUCCUUCUGGCUCCUAGGGUGCCUGGUUCUGUGGAGCUGGAGCCUGGUGAUGGAGGCUUUUCAGGCUUGUCAGGGAGGCAGCAAACUGCAGGAAUGCCUGGCACUGUGGGGCUGUCUGCAGCUAGUGGGGUGCCCGUGGCUCCCAGGGUGCCUAGGCCUGUGCAAGAGGAAACUGGCUCAGAAUUGUGGGGUGAAAGAGAGACAGUGGGCGGACCUGCAGAUGCCAAGGGUCCCACAAGGAUGGAGGUGCCCACCUCGACCAGGAUGCCUGGGCCCAUGGCGGAGAAGACUGGCUCUGGGGGUGUCUCAGGUUUGUUGGGAGGCAGACAGACUACAGGAGUGUCCAUGGCUGUGGGGCUGCUGGGGUCUGUGGGGGAGGGGACCAUCUUUGAGCAUGUCUCUGGCCUGUCUGGAAGAAGGCAGACUGCUGGGAGGCCUGUGGCUGCUAGAGGUUCCAUGGCCGUGGGAGUGCCCACAGCUCCCGGGCUUCCAGGGCCAAUGGUAGGGGAUACGGGCUCUGGGGAUGACGGCUCAGGCAUAUGGGGAAGGAGACUGGCCACUGAGGGGCCCACAGCUGCCAGGGUUCCUGGACCUGUGGAGGGGGAGACAGGCUCUGAAGGUGUCUCAGGCCUGUGGAGAAGGAGACACGGUGGAGCCAUUCCCGAGGCCGGGAGGGUGCCUCUGCCUCUGGGGGUGCUUGCAGCUGUAGGAGCUCCCAUGGCAGGGCGUGCGCCUGCUGCGGUGUGGGUGACUGGGUCCUCAGGAGCAGAAGCGGACGUGGGUGUCUCAGGUCUGACCGUGCUGAGGAGACAGUCCACAGGGGGAGUGGGGGCUUCAGAGGAUGAGACAGGAGGUGGGAAUAUUUUGGGACUGGCCGGGGGCAGCCAGGCUGUGGGGACAUCUCACACCUGUGUGCCUGGGGCCAGGUUAUGGAGCUGUCCAAGGUCUUUGGGGGAAGAAACAGCCUAUGAGAAUGCUCUAGGCAUGUCAGGGACAAGAACAGCUGUGGGGGUACCCUCAGUUUCAAGGGAGGAAAUAGGCCUUGGCCAUUUCAGAGACCACCUACAGCCAAGUGGGAGGAGGCUGGCUGGAGGAGUGUCUGCAGUCAGAGUGAGAGGGAGCAAUUUGGGAGAGAGUUAUGUGGGGGAGGCUAGAUUGAGGGGGGCGUUCCAGUAG